AGACGCGCCCAGACGGCCGCGAUGGCGCUGUUGGCCGGCGGGCUCUCCAGAGGGCUGGGCUCCCACCCGGCCGCCGCAGGCCGGGACGCGGUCGUCUUCGUGUGGCUUCUGCUUAGCACCUGGUGCACAGCUCCUGCCAGGGCCAUCCAGGUGACCGUGUCCAACCCCUACCACGUGGUGAUCCUCUUCCAGCCUGUGACCCUGCCCUGUACCUACCAGAUGACCUCGACCCCCACGCAACCCAUCGUCAUCUGGAAGUACAAGUCUUUCUGCCGGGACCGCAUCGCCGAUGCCUUCUCCCCGGCCAGCGUCGACAACCAGCUCAAUGCCCAGCUGGCAGCCGGGAACCCAGGCUACAACCCCUACGUUGAGUGCCAGGACAGCGUGCGCACCGUCAGGGUCGUGGCCACCAAGCAGGGCAACGCUGUGACCCUGGGAGAUUACUACCAGGGCCGGAGGAUUACCAUCACCGGAAAUGCUGACCUGACCUUUGACCAGACGGCGUGGGGGGACAGUGGUGUGUAUUACUGCUCCGUGGUCUCAGCCCAGGACCUCCAGGGGAACAAUGAGGCCUACGCAGAGCUCAUCGUCCUUGGGAGGACCUCAGGGGUGGCUGAGCUCUUACCUGGUUUUCAGGCGGGGCCCAUAGAAGACUGGCUCUUCGUGGUUGUGGUAUGCCUGGCUGCCUUCCUCAUCUUCCUCCUCCUGGGCAUCUGCUGGUGCCAGUGCUGCCCGCACACUUGCUGCUGCUACGUCAGGUGCCCCUGCUGCCCAGACAAGUGCUGCUGCCCCGAGGCCCUGUAUGCCGCCGGCAAAGCAGCCACCUCAGGUGUUCCCAGCAUUUAUGCCCCCAGCACCUAUGCCCACCUGUCUCCCGCCAAGACCCCACCCCCACCAGCUAUGAUUCCCAUGGGCCCUGCCUACAACGGGUACCCUGGAGGAUACCCUGGAGACGUUGACAGGAGUAGCUCAGCUGGUGGCCAAGGCUCCUAUGUACCCCUGCUUCGGGACACGGACAGCAGUGUGGCCUCUGAAGUCCGCAGUGGCUACAGGAUUCAGGCCAGCCAGCAGGACGACUCCAUGCGGGUCCUGUACUACAUGGAGAAGGAGCUGGCCAACUUCGACCCUUCUCGACCUGGCCCCCCCAGUGGCCGUGUGGAGCGGGCCAUGAGUGAAGUCACCUCCCUCCACGAGGACGACUGGCGAUCUCGGCCUUCCCGGGGCCCUGCCCUCACCCCGAUCCGGGAUGAGGAGUGGGGUGGCCACUCCCCCCGGAGUCCCAGGGGAUGGGACCAGGAGCCCGCCAGGGAGCAGGCAGGCGGGGGCUGGCGGGCCAGGCGGCCCCGGGCCCGCUCCGUGGACGCCCUGGACGACCUCACCCCGCCGAGCACCGCCGAGUCAGGGAGCAGGUCUCCCACGAGUAAUGGUGGGAGAAGCCGGGCCUACAUGCCCCCGCGGAGCCGCAGCCGGGACGACCUCUAUGACCAAGACGACUCGAGGGACUUCCCACGCUCCCGGGACCCCCACUACGACGACUUCAGGUCUCGGGAGCGCCCUCCUGCCGACCCCAGGUCCCACCACCACCGUACCCGGGACCCUCGGGACAACGGCUCCAGGUCCGGGGACCUCCCCUAUGAUGGGCGGCUACUGGAGGAGGCUGUGAGGAAGAAGGGGUCGGAGGAGAGGAGGAGACCCCACAAGGAGGAGGAGGAAGAGGCCUACUACCCGCCCGCGCCGCCCCCGUACUCGGAGACCGACUCGCAGGCGUCCCGAGAGCGCAGGCUCAAGAAGAACUUGGCCCUGAGUCGGGAAAGUUUAGUCGUCUGAUCUGACGUUUUCUACGUAGCUUUUGUAUUUUUUUUUUUAAUUUGAAGGAACACUGAUGAAGCCCUGCCAUACCCCUCCCGAGUCUAAUAAAACGUAUAAUCACAA